AGGGCCAGGAAGCGCGGAAGGAACCGCCGGGGGCCAUGGACGGAGCAGUGAUGGAAGGGCCGCUUUUUUUGCAGAGUCAGCGCUUUGGGACCAAGGUAGUCUGGCGCAUGGAUGCCGAACCUUAUCCGGGCUAGUAGUGGGUGGAGGAAGACCUGGGCCGUGCUCUACCCGGCCAGUCCCCACGGCGUAGCGCGGCUCGAGUUCUUUGACCAUAAGGGGUCGAGCUCUGGGGGUGGCCGAGGGAGCUCGCGCCGCCUGGACUGCAAAGUGAUCCGUCUGGCUGAGUGUGUGAGUGUGGCCCCCGUCACCGUGGAGACCCCCCCUGAGCCCGGCGCCACUGCCUUCCGCCUGGACACUGCUCAGCGCUCGCACCUGCUGGCGGCCGACGCGCCGUCCAGUGCAGCCUGGGUGCAGACGCUGUGCCGAAACGCCUUUCCGAAAGGCAGCUGGACUCUGGCGCCUACCGAUAACCCACCUAAGCUUUCUGCCCUGGAGAUGCUGGAGAACUCCUUGUACAGCCCUACCUGGGAAGGAUCCCAAUUCUGGGUAACGGUGCAGAGGACUGAGGCCGCCGAGCGCUGUGGCCUGCAUGGCUCCUACGUGCUGAGGGUGGAGGCUGAAAGGCUGACUCUCCUGACCGUGGGGGCCCAGAGUCAGAUACUGGAGCCACUCCUGUCCUGGCCCUACACUCUGUUGCGUCGCUAUGGCCGGGACAAGGUCAUGUUCUCUUUCGAGGCCGGCCGCCGCUGCCCCUCAGGCCCUGGAACCUUCACCUUCCAGACGGCACAGGGAAAUGACAUCUUCCAGGCAGUUGAGACUGCCAUCCACCGGCAGAAGGCCCAGGGAAAGGCCGGACAGGGGCACGAUGUUCUCAGAGCUGACUCCCAUGAAGGGGAGGUGGCAGAGGGGAAGUUGCCUUCCCCACCUGGCCCCCAAGAGCUCCUCGACAGUCCCCCAGCCCUGUAUGCUGAGCCCUUAGACUCCCUGCGCAUUGCUCCAUGCCCUUCCCAGGACUCCCUAUACUCAGACCCCUUGGACAGCACGUCUGCUCAGGCAGGAGAGGGAGUACAACGGAAGAAACCUCUCUAUUGGGACUUGUAUGAGCAUGCGCAGCAGCAGUUGCUGAAGGCCAAGCUGACAGACCCCAAAGAGGAUCCCAUCUAUGAUGAACCUGAGGGCCUGGCCCCAGUCCCUCCCCAGGGCCUUUAUGAUCUGCCUCGGGAGCCCAAGGAUGCAUGGUGGUGCCAAGCUCGGGUGAAGGAGGAGGGCUAUGAGCUCCCCUACAACCCUGCCACUGAUGACUACGCUGUGCCACCCCCUCGGAGCACAAAGCCCCUCCUUGCUCCCAAGCCCCAGGGCCCAGCCUUCCCUGAACCUGGUACUGCAACUGGCAGUGGCAUCAAAAGCCACAACUCAGCCCUGUACAGCCAGGUCCAGAAGAGCGGGGCCUCAGGGAGCUGGGACUGUGGGCUCUCUAGAGUAGGGACUGACAAGACUGGGGUCAAGUCAGAGGGCUCUACCUGAGAAGGACGGCAAGGCUGAGGUGGCUAAGGGGGACCAUGGGGAGGUGGCACUAGGGAUCAAAGAAGAUGGUUAGAACCAGCAGAAGCCAGAGGGUGGGAGGGGCCAUGCUGUGUGAGACCAGGGGACCAGAGGGAUGGGAGAGUCAAGGGAAGGACAAUCCCAGGAAGUCCUAAGAAGUGGGGCAGAUGGCAGGGCUGAGGAUGGGCUCUGCAUCCCCCAAAGCCAUCCCUUCCCUACUUCCCCAAAUGAAGGGACGGCUGUGGGACCAGGUCUGUGGAAAGUGGUGCAUGGUCAGAAUGGGUGCAGUUUGAGGGGCCUGUGUGGAGGCCUCAGGGAGAUGUUGGACUGUGCCUGGAUCCUUACUCCUGCAUUGUUCUUUGCCAGAGACCUAUUUAAAAAUUUUAAAAUUCUCAUUAAAGUCAGCUUGGGUUUAAGAA